CUACUUCCAACUUUUACCCCUCUACUCCUUUCCUAUCCUGAAAAAUACACCCUCCCAUCAUACCUGCCUCCCCCGCUUGCUGUUGUACCAGCCUUUUGUUUCAUCCCCAGCUGAGAUUUGAGAGGUGAAUAUUCACUUUCCCACAUACCCUUGCACACGUGAGCCAGACUUUUUCACCGAAAGUGCUCAGGCCAAAGUGUCAGGUGACUCUCAGCUGCCAGAUCCAGCGGUCACUUUUGCCCCUUAACGUGCGUGACUUGCUUUUGACACCUGCAAUGCUGCUUACCACUCUCUUCCUGAAGGGGUUGCCUCUUUUGGCUUCUAGGCCAACAUUCUCUUCAUAGUUCUUGUCCUCUGACCCACCCUUCUUCCUCUCCUCUGCUGAAUGCUUUUCUUCUCCCAGUUCCCUAAAUGCUAGUGAUCCCCUGGAUUCUGCCAUUGGCCUUUUUUCUCUGUGUAUGCUCUCCUUGGAUUAUCUCAUCCUGCAUAUGUGGAUUAGUCACAAAUCUGUAAAUCCCAGAUCUUUCUCUUAGGAUUCAGGACAACCAACUACUAGAUACCUUGACUUAAAUUUAUUAUGCCACUACCAGCUAUUCCAACUGAAAAAUUGAAUUGAGUGGAAAUCAUGUUGACUAUAGAGUAGUUUUCUCCUUCAUCUCCCUGCCUCCAGUCUUUCCUCCCUUCAAUCUUGCUUCUACAUUCCUGGUAGAAUUCUUUUUAAAACGGAAUGGUGACCUCAUUGCCUCACUUGUUAAAACCCUUCAGGGGUUCCUUACUGUCCCUUUGUAAUUAGGAUCUUACAAUAUUGAACUUUCCCUGAGUUGUACCCUGGAAAAUCUCCCCAUCCUUCAAUUUUCCAACCCUCACCCCCCACCCCCACCCUUUGGUGUUCUGGGAAACCACAAAGGACUAUCUUGUUCUCCAAUAUUCUGAGAUUAGACCCAUCUCUGUCCUUCCUGACUCCCAGAUGACUUCCUUGUUUACCUGCCUCUAUAGAACUCCAGACCCUUUCCUUUUCUUUGAGACAGCCCUCAUUAGUGUUUUAUUCCAGUAGCUUGAAGAAAAUCACCUCCUUAAUUGUCUGGUGCAUUUUGGCUCUCACAAGUCUUACCCUGUUAAUUUGUUACAGUUAUCAUUCUAUCAUGUUAUGUUUGUUUAUAAUAUAAUCUCUACAUUGUAUUAUUUAUAAUAAAUUACAAUAUAUUGUUCAUAAAUUGUUAGUAUAAAAUACUAUUUUAUGUUUAUACUUCCACUUUAAGUCCUUAGUGUUUAUAAAAUACUUGUAUUUAUAAACAAGGAUGAAUUAUAAAAUAAGUCUGUCCAAAUCUAUUUCUAGAUGCUUUUAAGAGGUGUUUUUUAGUAGUUGGAGGUUUUAUUAAUUAUGUUACCAACUAAACUGCUGAGACACCCAAAUAGAAUGACUUAAAUAAGAUAGAUGUUUAUUUCCUCCUUACAGAACAGUCCAGAUAUGAGCAGCCAGCAACUGGCAGGAUAGCACUCCUGUGCUACACACGUGAUUUCUAAGGUUGUCCUGCUGUCCCCAUUUCUAGCCCGCAGGAAAAAAGGAAAAGGAAGGCCAAGUCAAGUAGCCUUGUCUUGUAGCCUUGUCUUUAUGAAGGUUACCAGGAAAUUAGUUGAACUGCUUCUUACAUCCUGUUGGUCCCUCCUCAUUAGGUGGCCACAUCUGGCUGCAAAUGAGGCUGGGAAAUGUUAUCUCUAGAUGGGCACCUUUGCACCUAGCUAAACUGGGUGGUGAUGGUGGCAGGUGUAUGUUACUAAAUAAUGAUUUUGGGGGCACACUUAGUAGUUAUCAUAGAAAUGGAAGACUAUUUUGAUUAAAAAGUCAACUUGGGAGGAAAUGAGUGAUUAAAAAACAUCUGGGCCUACCCUAUAAGCUUCAGUACUUGCCAUAUGUAAGUAACAGGACUCAAUACUUCUUUCUUUUUUCCUUCUAGAAAAGUAUGCCAUGCAGAGUUAAGAGUAUGUAAAUUUAAAAGACAGUUUGUAGCUCUUACUCUCAACCAGUGCAUUUGUGGUGAAAAUGGGUGGCAUAGGAUACAUGUGCAUAUUACAAACAAAUGCUUGCAACAUGGAAUUCUCUCUACACUUUUUUGUCUCAUUACUUAUAUUUUCAGAUUCAGUACAACUUGUGGUAUCAGUUUAUCACCAUCUUCGAAAUAUUUUCUGAAAGAUGAUAUAUUUUCUAAGUGGAAGAAUUAUUCCUUUCCUGCUCUCUUGUAUUCCUCACUCUCAAAUGUCUUAGAUAAUUUGGGUCAAUUUCCUGGCUGAUGUCCCCUGGCCUACUAGUAAUGGAAUGAAUACAUGCUUGCCGACAUGCAGAUCCUCUCAGGCCAUGGUACAGGGCAGCCUCUAACCAUGAGCAGCUUCAGCUGUUUCCUGCUUUAUGCAGUACGGAUACUGUCAUGUUGUACAUAUAUUCUGAUACGGAAAAGUGUGGGAAAUGCUGUUUUAAUGGUUUAUGCCAAUUUCAUCUCUUUGUACUCCAAAUUUUUUACUAGAAAAUAAUUGUAAUAUGUAACAUCCUACCAUGGUAAAAGGUCAGUCCCCUUGGUAAAGAAGUAAAAAUUAUCUUGCUAUGUUAUCCACUUUGGAUGGACUGCAACUGUAAAAUAUCUAAGAUAUGAUGUUGUGUCCGGAAUUGGUGGGUUCUUGGUCUUACUGACUUCAAGAAUGAAGGGCUGGCCAACUGCUCCGAGUGCGGGGCCCACCAAGCCCACGCCCACCCGGAACUCCAGCUGGCCCGCAAGCACAGCACGCAGCCUUGGUUCCCGCUCACGCCUCUGCCUCCACACCUCCCUGCAAGCUGAGGGAGUGGGCUCCAGCCUUGGCCAGCCCAGAAAGGGGCUCCCACAGUGCAUUGGUGGGCUGAAGUGCUCCUCAAGUGCCACCAAAGUGGGAGCCCAGGCAGAGGAGGUGCCGAGAGCAAGCAAGGGCUUUGAGGACUGCCAGCACACAAUGUGACUACAGAUUAUUUGCCUAAAAAUAUCUAUACUUACGUUUAUAUGUCAGCCAUACAUAAUGGCAUCAGACCUUUCUAGCCCAUGUGGCCUAUAAUUAGGGUGACAGUAACACUUGGUUUUCCUGGAAACGUCCCUGGUUUUUGUUUACUAUUACUGCUUGUUGCUGGUCUCAGUUAUCACAGUUUUUUUUUUUUUUUGCAUUUAUACACUUUAUUGUCUUUUUAAAAAUUUUUUACAUAUAGUGAAGAUGGGGUCUUACUAUGUUCCCAGGCUAGUCUCGAACUCCUGGGCUCAAGCAAUCCUCCCAAAGUGCUAGGAUUACAGGCGUGAGUCACUGCACGGGGCCGUGUCAUUUUAGAUAUUAGCACUGCUUACCCUAAAUAAUUCUGGGCAGAAUGGUGGUAGUGGUCCAUGCUCCGUCUUUUCCAAACUACUUAAGAUAAGUAUGGGUGGAUCUUUAAGCUCUUGGAGGGCAAGGACUCUAUCUAUCUUGCUCUACUGUGUGUGUGUGUGUGUGUGUGUGUGUGUGGUGUGUGUGUAUGUGUGUGGUGUGUUCAGCACCUAGCACAUUACCUAAGCUAAACAUUUGAAAAUGUAAAUGAUUAUGAGCUUGAUGGCUUCAUGACAACACAGAUUUGGUAAAGUCUAUGAUGGGCAAGAUACUUUGUUGCCAACUACAAAUCCUAAAUACCUAACAGAGUGUAGCGUUUAGGAAUGAAUAGAUUAAUGAUUGGUCACCUCAGUCUUAUAUAUUUCUUAGCAUUUGCAGUCUCUAUCUAAAGAUAUUGUGGUCCAUCAACACAUUAGACAAUCCUACAAUUACAGUUGUAACAUGUUGUAUAUAAAGUCACACAAACAAGCAACUGUUUCUUGGGUAUAAUGAUCCGUGUUUACUGUUUUUUGAUUUUAUGAGGAAAAAAGAUGGCAUUUAAUUACUCCAAUAAUGAUCACAUCGUAGAUAGAUAAAUUCUAUCACUUGUAAGAUUUAGACCUUAAUUUGUAACCAAUGUAUGAUAUUUUAGGCUGGAAUUCCCAGUGGAUGUGCCAGGAAUGGCUACUGGAUGGCUGAAAUAUUCACUCCUUUGGGCAGGGCUGGAGACCCUUUGCCUGACUGUAUUCGCCCUCUUCAGUUUACCCCAGGGCAUAUAUAAAUGUCCUUUCCUCUGUGGGCCAUAAAGUGAAACAGAUUGGGAAACACUGUUAAUGACCUCUACAACCAAAAUAGCAGGUGCUUAAAUAAAUGCAGUGGCACCCUUGACAUUUGAGUAUGCAAAAUAAUUUUUCAAAAAUGUUAUCUUGGGCCAUUUUUUGAGAGUUAAAUAGAUGUGCUUUAUCAGAAAGUAAAUAUCCAAGAUUAUCAAAGUCAAAGACCAUAAUCUUCAAAGAAGCAAUUCAUCUAAAAUAAGUAACAACAUACUGAAUUAGAAAGCAUGUUCUCACAUGAAGUUCACAAAAAAGUCUCACAAAAAAAGAGAGAAAGAUAGUAUGUUUGUUUAUAUUUUGGACCUUCCCACCACAGGAAGGUUUAAGCGUGUUUAUGAACUGCAGGCUGCUCAAUUGCGAUUCAGUCCUACAUCUCUACUAAUGCUUUAUUGCAGGGGGAAAUGUUAGAAAUUAUAGCAUCAUGACAGUGGCUAUCUACUAAAAUUCUGCCAGUUAAGAUAAUUUGGGGAAAGGGAAGAAACCAUUAAUUCCAAGCACACCUUAGUUUGUGAAGGGCUUCCAGUUAAAUGUCCUAUCAGAUCUGCUUUUCUAAAGAUCAUUUGUUAUUUUCAUAAGAGCUGCACAAAUAGAUGCUAAGUACUUAGAAACAGAAUUAAAUAAAUCAAAUGUGAAUAAAACAUUUGUUUGUUUUAUCAAAUCCUUUGAAAUAGAACAAAAGUUAUAUUUAGCCAAAUUUACCAAUUUAUCACUAAAUCGAAAAUAAGGACUUGUUUGUAUUACUUCGAAAGGCCAACCCUUUAGGGGAAUUUUUAUUUAGCUCUAAAAUGUUUUUUAAUGUCAAUAAUGAAUUCCACUGCAAUAGCGAUUAUAUUGCCAAAGGUCAUUAAUGAUUUUUAAGUCUUCAUUACGCUUUAAUGAGAUUGAGAUUAAGAUCUCUGUAAUAUUUGACUGAUGUAUAGUUUAACUCUGUGUCUCCUCAUCUUUUGAUUUUCUUGCUUUUCUGUUCUCUCUUUUCUUCGUUGAUUUUUUUUUUCUUCUCAAAGCCUUCAUGAUCUUUAUUUUUCCCCUGUCACCACUACAUUUCAAAUCCUGGGUUUUCCUCAGGGGCCGCCACCUUCCCCAAAUUUUUCUGGACAUUUAAAUCCAAUUUUGUGGAAUUUUCAGGGUAGGAACAUUCAAUGAGCGGGCCUACCAUGUGUUCAACAUUAGACUGGGUGGUGUAUGUACCUUGUCACAGUGGGGUUUUAUUUCCAUUUCAUUGAUAAGGAAAAUGAAGGCCCAAGUUUACACAGUGAUGUGAAACAUUAUCUGUGUUCCUAUUGUACAGGUAAAAGGUGGAAAUAGGGGUGAAAACUCAAGCAAGCUAACUACUUAAGCCACAUUCUUAUCCAGUAUACUACCAACUUAAGAACUGAAUUUCUAGUUUAAAUUAGCUCUAUAAUAGAGACUCUAGGCUAUUUGUGUUUAAAUUAUUCCAUCUGUUAGAUAUCUUUAUACAGGUGCAAACUAUUUGCCCUAAUUAGCCCAUUAAUCUAUCCAUUUUAUUCAAUACCUUUUCUACCACUCACAACCUAGUUUUAACUACCUACAUAUAUCCUUUGCCUGGAGUCAUGCAAUAGCUGCUUUCCUGAUCUUAUAUCUUCCCUCACUAAUCUGUAUGCUAAGCCCAGAGUAAUCUUUAAAAGGGACAAAUUUAAUUUUCAUCAACCUCCAAUCUGCAGCUGAAAACACACCAGUGACUUAAAACUGCCCUUAGUUUGAUGACAUCAAACUAUGCUUCUAAGCAUCAUCUCACACUGCAUGUUCCUGUGACUCUUCAAGCUUUGGGCACUAGCCUUCUUUCAGUUCUCUGGUCAUUCUUUGUUCCCCUCUCUCCACAGGGCCUUUGCACAUUCUGGGCCACCAUACUCCUAUACUCUUUCUUCACACCUCCCUUCCAUCACGAUUUCCUCAGAAAAUUCCUCCCUGAUCUUGCCAGCUGGAGGAAACACCCCAUUAUGCACUUUCAUAGUACCAUGCAAGCAGGGGAAGGUCCAAGCUUCCUGGGAUCUGAAAUUUUUGUAAUUUGAGGGGCUGUCUUUAAGAAAAAUAAAAUUAGAGAUACAAAUAUGAGUAUAGGGCCUUGGAAGCGGUCAGUGCGAGGAUAGGGUCCUGACCCUUAACCUUUCACUGCAUGGCAAAUCUACCUCAGCCUGUACCUCUUGUUGGUAGCUCUUCACAUUGACAAUUCAAUUUAUAUACACAACUCGGUGAAUAUUUCUUUCCCCUACACUAUGCACUGUGUGAGAGAGGAAAUAUGUCUGAAUUUACUCCCCAAGCUUUCUCCAGGAAUUUGCAUAGUGUUAACACUUGAGUAUACAGUAUAUAUUUCUUGGGUAAAGGAAUAAAUGAGCAAAUGAAUAAUUAGAAGAAGACUUAGAGUUAAUGCUUAUAAUGCCCGUAUAAAAUUGUCCGAAUUUUUUGGAACCCAAAGCCAAGUGGAGAACAUCUGGGUUCCAUGGCUCAUACCAUUUCAUCAUGAAAGACAAACUUCUCAGUACCAGGUGGUAAAGAUGAAUGUUGAUAGGUUUAUUUAUAUAAAGCACCUUAUUCCACACAAUGAAUAAUAACCAGCAGCUGUUACUCAGUGCUUACCAUGUGCUGGGCACUUGCUCAACACUUGCACAUGGUAUUCUGCCUUAACACAUAUGGCAUUCACCACUAACUGCAGAGUUACUCUCAGUCAGAAUUUCUGCCUCCAUGGUCCAUGCAAUGCAGAAGGGCAGAAAACCCCAUGCAGGACAAGGAAAAGGAGGCCUGAGGUGCUGGCACCUUCACUGUCUCAAGGGUCCUCCCUCUCUGGAGCUCCUUCCUCUCUGCCAUUUUAUAUCACCUUUUAUGUGCUAAAAUGGUGUUUGUUUGCCACUGCCCCAGAGAUGAUACUGGCUUAUCACCUGCCCUCUGCUUAGUUCUUGGUAUUAUCUCCUAGUGAGGGUAUGCCCAAGCUUACCUUUGUCUUUGUUUUCCUGUAGAGUGCUUAAUUAUGAGUCAAACUACAUGCAGGUGGUCUAUCCGAAUGAGUUAGCAUCAGAAUGACCUGUUAAAAAGAGUUCUAAUAUGUUGCCCAGCUGGACAUUGAAAAAUGCCUGUUAGAGUUGUUGAUCAUUUUGACUUUGGUAUAAUUAAUAGUGACCUUUUCUCACUGCCAGUAUUUGGUUCAGGUUGGGUGCCUUCUGAGCACCCUUCUGGAAUGCUGUACAGUUGUGAGUGAUUCAUUCUGUUAACAAAUCUUUAUUAAGUGCCUAAUCUGUGCUGUGCCCUGAGGAUACGCAGAUAAAAGAAACUGUCCUCCCAUUAGGUGGAGGCAUUGAAACCCAAGUGGAGGAAGACAGGGAGACAGAACUGACAGUUCUGCAAGUAUCAUGAGCAGCCAUUGUCUGACUUUGCAUUCAUUUCUGGUCUUACUGGCUAGAAUCUCCUAAUAAACUACCAAGUAAUCCUUUUAACUGAAUAAGCUACCUAUCCAAGGAUUAGAAUUUGUAUCUGAGUGUUUUUCUCUCAUACUAACUUUGAGAACUUUUUGAGGGUUAGUGAGGUAAGCACCAGAGCAAGAUACUCAGGUUCUUUUCCAGCAAUCUGUACCAAACCAGGAAUAAGGACUGACAGGCUCCCAGCUGUCUGUCACCAGAGCAGAUAUUUAUGGGUUUAUGAUCAGAGGUUCUUUUGGUCCCAAAAAGUAACUGGAAAAGAAUGUGGCAACUUCCUGGGACCAUGGAAAGCUGCUUGGGUGUCAGGGAUAUGCUAUGCCAGGUAUAUGCUAGAAGAAAUACUAUUAAAUGUCAGUAAACUUAAAAGGAAAAUGGUCAAGUUUAAUCUAAGAUGUCCAUUUUGCAGAUGGAAAGAAGCAGGGAAUUUAAAAAUGCAAGCAAAGCUCCCAUUACAAAUCCUACUAACUGUCUCAUAAACUGGAUGAAGUUAGGCGAUAAAGUUGAACCAAAUUCUUCACUCAGUUUGGGAUGACUUUCUCUGGAGCCUUUAUUAAGGUCUCUUAGCUGCCAGACUGUUUUAGGGACUAAUGAAACUAUUGUCAUUAUCCCUUGCUCUUUUUAUGUUUCCUCUAAGUUGCUUUCUCAGUAAGGACAGCUUUUAAUUUUUUAAAAAAUUAUUUCCCUUUUUAAUCCCCAGAACCCUAUAGCAAAAACUCCAUAAUUAUUUGUUAAAGUUUCUAGUAGAGGGUACACUAAGUGGGGUCUAUAGAUACUGAAGCUCUUGUGAAAUUCUGCUGGCCUGAGUUCAUGAUUUAAGGGAAUGCUGGUGAUAGCUUGUAGAAGAAACUGAGAUUGUAUGGAAUAAAAUGUGGAAGCCAUUGAUUUUAGAGCCUCUUUUUUAUUGUUCUGUGAAUAAAAUCUCAUUUGUAAGCCCUCAAAUGUGGGCCUUGACUUUUAGAAUUGAGAGCUAGAAGUAAAAACAAAUUCACAGCAGUGUACUAACACAUUUUUGUUAAUUCCUAAGAUAUUUUGCUUUAGACCUAUUAACAUAUUUAGAGUUAUGUUCCUUAGUUCUGAGGCAAAUUUGCUCUGUGAAUAGCACUACACUAGGAAGAAAUCCUAAAAGAGACAUUAACAUGUAAUUUGUGUAAAGUUCUUUUUAUAUUUCACAAGUUAUGAAUUUUCUAUAGUCCUUUUAAGUGUUAAAUGGAUUUAUAAAAAGCUUUUGGUGGUUAGCAAAAUGGGUGGUUUUUGCCUAAUGUGAAAUCUGAGAUUGAUAAGUUUUAUAUAAGGAGUGUUUUUUUAAAUCUUGAGAUUUUUUAUGUAAAAAAAUUGUUUCAGUUAUUUUUGAUAUCUAAACCAAAAUAGCAUUAGAAAGGAGCUAUUUUAAAAGUUUAAUUUCUUAUCAUAAUCUUUUAAGAGGGAGUGACACCAGUGACUUACGUUUCGUUUCUAUAUAGAAUUAUAUCAGCUAUAGAGUAUAUUGUAUACUUGUAAUACCCAUAACUAUUAACACUUAAAUAAUACAGUAAUACAGAGGCCUAUUGGGAAAAAAAAAAAAAAAAAAACUAAAUCAUUCCUUUUUCCCCUAUUGCUUCUGAAGCAUUUUUUAUUUUCUUUAACUGUAUAAAUUUUUGAUAACUGAUUUGGGUGUGCUGUGUGAGUAUCUGUGUGUACAUACACAUAUGUGCUUACGUGUCUGUUGAGUGUUAGGGAAGGCUUGUUGUAGAGAUGGUGUAGCUCAUUAUAAACUUUAGUUUGUUCUCAUUUGAUUUAUUUCAAUGAAAGAUUUGAGAAUUUGAUCCUCGUAAGUCUCUUGCAUGUUCUCCAUUUGCCCAGGUUGACCAAGAGGGCUAACUUUUUUCCCUGCAGAAAGAAAGUGAAAGUUGAUAUUUGAUUGGGUAGUUAAUUCAUGCCUACAUGAAAAAUUACAGGCCAGAUGUGGUGGCUCAUGCCUGUAAUCCCAACACUUUGGGAGGCCAAGGCGGAUGAAUCACUUGAGUCCAGGAGUUCAAGACCAGCCUAGGCAACAUGGUGAAACCCUGUCCCUACAAAAAAUACAAAAAAUUAGCUGGGCUACUCGGGAGGCUGAGGUAGGAGAAUCACCUGAGCCCAGGAGGUCAAGGCUGCAGUGAGCCAAGAUCACGCCACUGCACUCUAGCCUGGACAACUGGAGUGAGACCCUAUUUCAAAAAAAACAACAAAAAAGAAAAACUAAGUAUAAUUGAGUGUUAUAUUGAUUACAUUAAUCAAGCCAUUUGCUUCUUUAUACAUUAAAUUCUUAUUUAAAUAAUAUUUCAAAGCCAUUUGGCUUCCUUCUUUUAAUAGGGGUACUAAGACCUCCUAGUGCAGAUAAACUUUUAAAGGUUUUUUUUGUUUGUUUGUUUUGUUUUGUUUUGUUUUGUUUUUUGAGAGAGAGAGAGUCUUGCUCUGUUGCCCAGGUUGGAGUGCAAUGGCACAAUCUCAGCUCACUACAACCUCCGCCUCCCAACUUCAAGCAAUUCUUCUUCCUCAGCCUCCUGAGCAGCUGGGAUUCCAGGCAUCUGCCACCAAGCCCGGCUAAUUUUUAAAUUUUUAGUAGAGUCAUGGUUUCACAUGUUGGUCAGGCUGGUCUUGAACUCCUGACCUCAGGUGAUCUGUCCUCCUCAGCCUCCCAAAGUGCUGGGAUUACAAGCGUGAGCCACUGCACCCGGCCAACUUUUAAAGUUUUAAUUUAGGUGAUUAUAUUUUUCUGUUUUAAUGCUAGGGUUUCUUUUAUUGCUUAUAACAAUCUCAUGAAUAUAUGUUUUCUAGCAGUCACCAAGCUACCCACAUUUACCCUGGCUAACAAAUGGGAACAAAGAGCAAGAUUUGAAUCCAGGUCUCUUGGGCAUCGGAGUUGUGCUCUUUCUAGUAUCAUUUGCCACCUCUUCAUAUAAUUUUUUUUUUGGGGGAGAUGGAGUUUUGCUCUUGUUACCCAGGCCAGGGUGCAGUGGGGCGAUCUUGGCUCGCUGAAACCUCCGCCUCUCAGGUUCAAGCUAUGCUCGUGCUUCAGCCUCCCAAGUAGCUGGGAUUACAGGUGCUCGCCACCACACCUGGCUAAUUUUUUGUAUUUUUACUAGAGACCGGGUUUCAUCAUGUUGGCCAGGCUGGUCUCGAGCUCCUGACCUCAGGUGAUCCACCUGCCUUGGCCUCCCAAAGUGCUGGGAUUACAGACAUGAGCCACUGCGUCUGGCCAAUAAUUUUGACUUAAAUACAUCUAAAAGAAUAAAUAAAAUUAAAUGCCACAUAUUUAUCAUUAGUCAUUUAUUCCAGGAUUACUCUAUGUGCGUGGUGCUACAUGCUAGUUCAAAAUUCAACGAAUUGGUCUAGUCAUCUUCAGUAAAGACUAAGACAGACUUUUCUCCUCAAUGAUUCUUUUUUUCUUUUUUAAAUUCAGAUUCAGCAAACAUCUUUGGGGGCUUACUUUGUGCCAGACCCUAAACCAGGUGUUCCUAAUACGUUACACUGUGAGGUGGUUUUUAUUAUUAAGAUUUUACCAAUGAGGCAUGAAUGUUAGAGAGGUAAUAAUAUAAGCAAUCAUUUAAAAACAUACUUGAACUUAGAAUGUAGUAUAGCAUGAAUAGUUACAAUAGGCUACAAUCAUAUCUACCUUCACUAUCCUAUUUCUGUUGAAAGGCAGUUUAGGCAGUAAAAUAAACAAAGGUUGAGAUCUGGUUUCUUUAUUUUAACAGCUUUAUGGAGAUAAAAUUUACAUACCAUACAAUUUACUCAUUUGAAGUAUAUAAUUCAGUGUUUUUUAGUGUAAUCACAGAAUUGUCCAACAACCAUGUCUUCUGAUUUUUGAACUGUUACUGAUUUUUUUUCAUUACUACUAACCAUACAUUUGAAUAAGAAAACAGGAUCAUAAUUCUAAAAGGGUUAUAUUCAACCCUGUUGUUUUCAGAUUUAGUUUUGUUCAACCAAAGUCCAAUAACUUUCCCUUUUCAGUUCUACUACAAAAAGCUUCCUUGACUUCCAUGAGAAAUGUUUGCUUACAGGAAUGUUAAGCUGAUUUUCAUGUGUGCCAUUGACAAGGAGAAGCUUUGGAAUGUGAAAUCCACUUCCGCAUAAUGUAAUUAUUUAAGUCUUUUGCAAUAGAUGUACUAUAAAAGAGAAAUCAAAGAAUAUAUGCGAUUAAUACUUACUAAAUAUAUGUUUUUCAAGUUAAAAAACAAAAAUCCCUUGAUAACCAUUUAUAGCCAUUCUGAGUCCUGAUUCACUAAGGAGAUCAAACCUCAAGAUAUGGAUAGGAUGCAGAGAAACCAGGUGCUGAUCCCUUCUCUCAUUGGCUUAAGUUCACAUUAGAAAGAAUCGUAUUGUUAUGAUGGCCAUACUUCCCAAAGCAAUAUGUAGAUACAGUGCUAUUCCUAUCAAACUACCAGUGUCAUUUUUCACAGAAUUAGAAAAAAACGAUUCUAAAAUUCAUAUGGAACCCAAAAAAAGCCAAAUCACCAAAGCAAUCCUAAACACAAAGAAUAAAGCUGGAGAUAUCACAUUAUGUGACUUCAAACUAUACUACAAGACUACAGUAACCAAAACAGCAUGGUACUGAUACAAAAGCAGACACACAGACCACUGGAACAGGACAGAGUCCACAAAAUUACACACAUACAACCACCUGAUCUUUGUGACAAAGUCGACAGUAACAAACAAUGGGGAAUGGACUCCCUAUUCAAUAAAUGGUGCUGGAAUAACUGGCUAGCCUUAUGCAGAAGAUUGAAACUGGACCCCGUCCUUUCACCAUAUACAAAAACUAACUCACGAUGGAUUAAAGGACUUAAAGGUAAGACCUAAAACAAUAAAAACUCUGAAGAAAACCUAAAAAAUACUAUUCUGGAUGUUGGCCUUGGCAAAGAAUUUAUGACUAAGUCCCCAAAGGCAAUUGCAACAAAAACAAAAAUUGACAAGUGGGACCUAAUUAAACUAAAGAGCUUCUGCACAGCAAAUUAAACUGUCAACAGUAAACAGACAGCAUACAGAAUGGGAGAAAAUAUUUGCAAACUAUGCAUCUGACAAAGGUCUAAUAUCUAGAAUCUAUAAGGAACUUAAAUCAGCAAGCAAAAAACAAUCCCAUUAAGAAAUGGGCAAAGGACAUGAACAAACACUUCUCAAAAGAAGACAUACAUGCAGCCAACAAAUAUAUGAAAAAAUGCUCAGCAUCACUAAUCAUUAGAGAAAUGCAAAUCAAAAAGUCAGUGAGAUACCCUCUCACACCAGAAUGGCUAUUAUUAAAAAGUCAAAAAACACCAGAUGCUGGCAAGGUUGCAGAGAAAAGAAAACACUUACGCACUGCUGGUGGGGAUGUAAAUUAGUUCAGCCACUGUGGAAAGCAGUGUGUAGACUUCUCAAAAAAGUUAAAACAGAACUAUAAUUCAACCCAGCAAUCUCUAUUGUGUAUAUACCCAAAGGAAAACAAAUCAUUCUACAAAAAAGAUGUGUACUUGUAUGUUCAUUGCAGCACUAUUCACAAUAGCAAAGACAUGUAAUCAACCAAGAUGCCCGUUGACAGUGGACUGGAUUUUUUUUUUAAUAUGGUACAUAUACACCAUGGAAUACUAUGCAACCAUAGAAAAGAAUAUAUCAUGUUUUUUGCAGCAACAUGGAUGCAGCUGCAGGCCAUUAUCCUAGGCAUAGUAAUACAGAAACAUAAAACCAAAUACCACAUGUUCUCACUUAUAAGUGGGAGCUAAACACUGAAUACACAUGGAUACAAAGAAGGGAACAAUAGACACAGGGGCCUGCUUAAUAGGGGAGAGAAAGGAGGGGAGUUGGGUUGGAAGGCUCCCUAUUAGGUACUAUACUCAUUACCUUGAUUGGGGGUCCCCAACCCCUGGGCCACGGACUGCUGCUGAUUCAUGGCCUGUUAGGAACCGGGUCGCACAGCACCAGGUGAGCAGUGGGAGAGUGAGCAAAGCUUCAUCUGUAUUUACAGCCACUCCCCAUUGUUGACAUUACUGCCUUAGCUCUGCCUCUUGUCAGAUCAGCAGCAGCAUUAGAUUCUCGUAGGAGUGUGAACCCUAUUGUGAACUGUGAAUUCAAGGGAUCUAGGUUCUGCUAUCCUUGUGAGAAUCUAAUGUCCGAUGAUUUGUCACUGUCUUCCAUCACUCCCAGAUGGGACCGUCUAGUUGCAGGAAAAGCUCAGGGAUCGCGCUGAUUCCACAUUAUGGAGUCCCCGGGCCCCAGGCUGCAGACUGGUACCUGUCGAGAGCUGUUAGGAACUGGGCUUCACGGCAGUAGGAAUGUUUACCCUUGCGGAAGUUGCAUCACUUAAUGACAUUCAGCCAACUUACCGAAUCCUGAAACCAUGGUGGGAUGUGUUUAUGGAUUACCUAGCUGUUGUUAUGUUAAUGGUAGCCAUCUUUGCAGGAACCAUGCAACUUACCAAAGAUCAGGUGGUCUGUUUGCCAGUAUUGCCAUCUCCUGUAAAUUCAAAGGCACAUACACCACCAGGAAAUGCCGAGGUCACCACCAACAUCCCAAAGAUGGAAGCAGCCACCAACCAAGACCAAGAUGGGCGGACAACAAACGACAUUUCCUUUGGGACAUCUGCUGUGACACCUGACAUACCUCUCAGAGCCACAUAUCCUCGCACAGAUUUCGCACUUCCAAAUCAGGAGGCAAAGAAAGAGAAGAAAGAUCCAACAGGUCGAAAAACAAACUUGGAUUUUCAGCAAUAUGUAUUUAUUAAUCAAAUGUGUUACCAUCUGGCCCUUCCGUGGUAUUCUAAGUACUUUCCAUACCUAGCUCUUAUACAUACUAUUAUUCUCAUGGUCAGUAGCAACUUUUGGUUCAAAUAUCCCAAAACAUGCUCAAAAGUAGAACAUUUUGUUUCAAUAUUAGGAAAGUGCUUUGAAUCCCCUUGGACGACAAAAGCGUUGUCUGAGACAGCAUGCGAAGACUCAGAGGAAAACAAGCAGAGAAUAACAGGUGCCCAGACUCUACCAAAGCAUGUUUCUACCAGCAGUGAUGAAGGGAGCCCCAGUGCCAGUACACCAAUGAUCAAUAAAACUGGCUUUAAAUUUUCAGCUGAGAAGCCUGUGAUUGAAGUUCCCAGCAUGACAAUCCUGGAUAAAAAGGAUGGAGAGCAGGCCAAAGCCCUGUUUGAGAAAGUGAGGAAGUUCCGUGCCCAUGUGGAAGAUAGUGACUUGAUCUAUAAACUCUAUGUGGUCCAAACAGUUAUCAAAACAGCCAAGUUCAUUUUUAUUCUCUGCUAUACAGCGAACUUUGUCAACGCAAUCAGCUUUGAACACGUCUGCAAGCCCAAAGUUGAGCAUCUGAUUGGUUAUGAGGUAUUUGAGUGCACCCACAAUAUGGCUUACAUGUUGAAAAAGCUUCUCAUCAGUUACAUAUCCAUUAUUUGUGUUUAUGGCUUUAUCUGCCUCUACACUCUCUUCUGGUUAUUCAGGAUACCUUUGAAGGAAUAUUCUUUCGAAAAAGUCAGAGAAGAGAGCAGUUUUAGUGACAUUCCAGAUGUCAAAAACGAUUUUGCGUUCCUUCUUCACAUGGUAGACCAGUAUGACCAGCUAUAUUCCAAGCGUUUUGGUGUGUUCUUGUCAGAAGUUAGUGAAAAUAAACUUAGGGAAAUUAGUUUGAACCAUGAGUGGACAUUUGAAAAACUCAGGCAGCACAUUUCACGCAACGCCCAGGACAAGCAGGAGUUGCAUCUGUUCAUGCUGUCGGGGGUGCCCGAUGCUGUCUUUGACCUCACAGACCUGGAUGUGCUAAAGCUUGAACUAAUUCCAGAAGCUAAAAUUCCUGCUAAGAUUUCUCAAAUGACUAACCUCCAAGAGCUCCACCUCUGCCACUGCCCUGCAAAAGUUGAACAGACUGCUUUUAGCUUUCUUCGCGAUCACUUGAGAUGCCUUCACGUGAAGUUCACUGAUGUGGCUGAAAUUCCUGCCUGGGUGUAUUUGCUCAAAAACCUUCGAGAGUUGUACUUAAUAGGCAAUUUGAACUCUGAAAACAAUAAGAUGAUAGGACUUGAAUCUCUCCGAGAGUUGCGGCACCUUAAGAUUCUCCACGUGAAGAGCAAUUUGACCAAAGUUCCCUCCAACAUUACAGAUGUGGCUCCACAUCUUACAAAGUUAGUCAUUCAUAAUGACGGCACUAAACUCUUGGUACUGAACAGCCUUAAGAAAAUGAUGAAUGUCGCUGAGCUGGAACUCCAGAACUGUGAGCUAGAGAGAAUCCCACAUGCUAUUUUCAGCCUCUCUAAUUUACAGGAACUGGAUUUAAAGUCCAAUAACAUUCGCACAAUUGAGGAAAUCAUCAGUUUCCAGCAUUUAAAACGACUGACUUGUUUAAAAUUAUGGCAUAACAAAAUUGUUACUAUUCCUCCCUCUAUUACCCAUGUCAAAAACUUGGAGUCACUUUAUUUCUCUAACAACAAGCUCGAAUCCUUACCAGUGGCAGUAUUUAGUUUACAGAAACUCAGAUGCUUAGAUGUGAGCUACAACAACAUUUCAAUGAUUCCAAUAGAAAUAGGAUUGCUUCAGAACCUGCAGCAUUUGCAUAUCACUGGGAACAAAGUGGACAUUCUGCCAAAACAAUUGUUUAAAUGCAUAAAGUUGAGGACUUUGAAUCUGGGACAGAACUGCAUCACCUCACUCCCAGAGAAAGUUGGUCAGCUCUCCCAGCUCACUCAGCUGGAGCUGAAGGGGAACUGCUUGGACCGCCUGCCAGCCCAGCUGGGCCAGUGUCGGAUGCUCAAGAAAAGCGGGCUUGUUGUGGAAGAUCACCUUUUUGAUACCCUGCCACUCGAAGUCAAAGAGGCAUUGAAUCAAGACAUAAAUAUUCCCUUUGCAAAUGGGAUUUAAACUAAGAUAAUAUAUGCACAGUGAUGUGCAGGAACAACUUCCUAGAUUGCAAGUGCUCACGUACAAGUUAUUACAAGAUAAUGCAUUUUAGGAGUAGAUACAUCUUUUAAAAUAAAACAGAGAGGAUGCAUAGAAGGCUGAUAGAAGACAUAACUGAAUGUUCAAUGUUUGUAGGGUUUUAAGUCAUUCAUUUCCAAAUCAUUUUUUUUUUUCUUUUGGGGAAAGGGAAGGAAAAAUUAUAAUCACUAAUCUUGGUUCUUUUUAAAUUGUUUGUAACUUGGAUGCUGCCGCUACUGAAUGUUUACAAAUUGCUUGCCUGCUAAAGUAAAUGAUUAAAUUGACAUUUUCUUACUAUAUCACCUUUUUUGAGGGGUCUUAAUUUACUUUGCUUAAUUGGUGCAAUAUUGCUUUAACUCCGUUCACUAAAGACAAACACAUCAAGUCCAAACUUGUAAAUUUAGAUUUGCUGAAAUACUGAUUUAUUUCCUGUUUUAAUUUAAAGUGCCUCAAGUAAGCACCUCUCACAACAGUUGACUGGUACUGCUGCUCCUGAGCACCUCGUGUCAUAGAUUUUAUACUCUUACAGACUUGGAAUGCAGUAGAGGUAUGUGGAUUUUUAGGGGUUUUGUUUUUUUAAGAAUAAGUAACAAGAAAUAACACAUUUCUUAAUAAUAGCUUUUUUGACAUAGUUUGGAGUUCUGAUUAUAUGGUACAUUUUUCUACCAGUAAUAUAGGGUUGCCAAUAAAUAGAAAAUGUUUUCUAAAAAUAAAUUUUAUUACAACAAAAUAAAAAUUUUAAUGACUUAUUAACACAACCUCCAGUAUCACCACCAUUUGGAAGAUAACACAGAAUCACAAGUAUCAUUUAAUUUCUUGCCCUUUUCAGUGUUGUUCUGGUGUUGGUGGGAAAAUAAUAGGAAAUGUAGUUCAUUGGGUAGGGAAACUCUUACCUUUCCCUAUCUUAAU